AUGCGCCCUGGGCCACAGGCAGCAGCGGAGGCGGGGAAGGAACAACUUUCCCUCCGCCCUCUAACCACAAGGGCGGGGUGGGGCGGCCUCGCUGGGGUCGGGCUCCUCCACUUUCCCAGCUGGGAUCCCCUGCCGGAGCUGGCGUGGGGGCCGGGGAGGGGGACCAGAGGGGCUUCCUUCUCUCCCCAAGCCCCGCCAGAUGUUGGAAAGGCAAACAAUAGGGGAAACGCGGAGAAACAAAAGGCCAUUCGCCACGAUCUCAGUCGGCUGCGCAUCGUCAGCCCCGGGGGCGACCUGGCUGACGGUGCGGACUUCCCCUACGCUGCCCCAAGCCGAGACUCCUCCCUCAGGAUCAGGACGCCCAAGCGUUGUCCCCCAGCCCAGGCGCACUUUUGUAAAAGUUUGUCUUCCCGCCACCCACAGCCCAACACGCACCCUGCAGGCGUCCGCGGCUGGGGAUGGGCUCGGAGUCUUGCACCCCGAAAGAAGGACGAUCUUAUUGAUUUAUAUCUUUUCAAAUCAAGGACAAAUCAAGAUCCCGGGGUGGAAAGUGGGCGACCCUUGUUCCUGCCGGGAAGUGCACACGAGGAGCCGGCCAGAAACCCAGGCGCCGGCAGGGGUCUGAAGAGGACUCCAGCCCCGGAAGCCCGUGGCCGGCGGGCAGAAGACCGGUCCGCCGCCUCCCGCACCUUCUUGCACCCGCGCCCAGGUGCGCCCCAAACCUCGCCGCCCGCCCGGGCGAGAUCGGGAGCGAGCAGCCACCGGGCUGCGCCGCCUCCCCUAGCUUGGAGCGGGUUCUUACUCACCGUGGGGUUUUACCUCCAGCCCAGGGCCCGGUCGGCUCCCUUCGCCGGGUCAGCUGCAGCCAGCGCGAAAGAAAAUGGUGAGCUCGGGGCAGGUGGGGCGUCGCUUGCCAAUCCACGCAAGGGACUCUGCCGCCGGUGCGCGAGGUCCCGGCGAGCCAACCGGCGGACGGGCGAGCGCCUGGCUCCAGCUGCAGCCGCCGUCGCUCCGGAGCAGCCCCCUCAUGCACCCAGCGCGCCGCGCAGCCGGCCGGGGCUCGACUGUCUCGCGGGGACGCCGAGCGGGGACCCCUGGCGGCCGCCUGCGGUAUGGCAGCACCGUGGAGAGAAAAGUCGUCUUUGGGAUCAUCUUCCCUCCGGAAAGAGAUGGGACAUGACCAGUCUAAGGGGGCUUCCAGCCUUGCAGAAAAGACACUGGGCCAGGGCAGUGAAGAAGGUGUCAGAUCAGAAAGGAUGAUCUCUGGGUCCACAACGGCCACUUCCAAGGCACCUAGAGAGGGGGAAACAGUUUGCCUUCCCCAGGAUUUUCUGAUUGUUGAAAAAUACCAUGAACUGCCUGACACAGAGCGGAGCAUAAAUCAUUGGAAAAUACUCAGAUUCUAGUGGAUUUACUAGAACACACUGGGAGUCAUGGAUGAACCUGGAUUUUAAAGCUCAACCCACAGCCCGCCACUCUCUACUUGUGUGGUCUUGGUCUAUCUACAACCUUAAAGCCUCAGUAUUCUCCUCCGUAAAUUGGCGGGGAGCAAUAUCACCCUUGCAGGGUGAUGGUUACGGGUAAACUACAUUUGAAACGUUUUUAUAGUUUAUAGUAACAGAAAUCAAAUAUGAGCUUCCUGCCUUCUGGAGAAAAAGAAUUGGAUCUUUCACAUUUUUCUAUUACCCAUAUGAUCACAUCUUAAUGCAUAUUGAUUGAACUGUACCAAAUGACGAAGUACUGCAUUUUACCAUUCUUACUACACACUUCAAAGAGGUGUGGAAAUAUAUUAAGUAGAAAUUAGGAUAUAUAGAGAAAACAUCCCUCCUCCAAAAGAGGUUUCUGCAACUAACUACGAAGUGAGAACUUCUAAAAUCACUUACAUCUUUUGCAAUAUCAUCUCAGAUAUUGUAAGAAACAUUUAAUAAAUAGUCAUGACUUAAUGAUAUCAA